ACAGAGUCUGCAGGUCGGGCGGUAGCGACAGGUCAGAGCUGCGGCCUGAGCAGCCAGCGUCCGGCAUGAAGGUCUGGGGUCUGGCUGCUGCCUGCUUCUUGCUCCAGCACCAUGGAAUGCCUGCGCAGUUUACCCUGCCUCCUGCCCCGCGCGAUGAGACUUCCCCGGCGGACGCUGUGUGCCCUGGCCUUGGACGUGACCUCUGUGGGUCCUCCCGUUGCUGCCUGCGGCCGCCGAGCCAACCUGAUUGGAAGGAGCCGAGCGGCGCAGCUUUGCGGGCCCGACCGGCUCCGCGUGGCAGGUGAAGUGCACCGGUUUAGAACCUCUGACGUCUCUCAAGCCACUUUAGCCAGUGUAGCCCCAGUAUUUACUGUGACAAAAUUUGACAAACAGGGAAACGUUACUUCUUUUGAAAGGAAGAAAACUGAAUUAUACCAAGAGUUAGGUCUUCAAGCCAGAGAUUUGAGAUUUCAGCAUGUAAUGAGUAUCACAGUCAGAAACAAUAGGAUUAUCAUGAGAAUGGAGAAAUAUUCUCUACUCUUGGAAUCAGUAGCUAGCAUUCUUCAAAACAGUGUCUCUUUCAUGGAGAGACAGACAGAGCAAUGGCUGUUCCGGGAACUCCCUUCACAGUUGUCUGGAGAGGGUCAACUCGUUACAUACCCUUUACCUUUUGAGUUUAGAGCUAUAGAAGCACUCCUGCAAUAUUGGAUCAACACCCUUCAGGGGAAACUUAGCAUUUUGCAGCCACUGAUCCUUGAGACCUUGGAUGCUUUGGUGGACCCCAAACAUUCUUCUGUAGACAGAAGCAAACUGCACAUUUUACUACAGAAUGGCAAAAGUCUAUCAGAGUUAGAAACAGAUAUUAAAAUUUUCAAAGAGUCAAUUUUGGAGAUCUUGGAUGAGGAAGAGUUGCUAGAAGAGCUCUGUGUAUCAAAAUGGAGUGACCCACAAGUCUUUGAAAAGAGCAGUGCUGGGAUUGACCAUGCAGAAGAGAUGGAGUUGCUGUUGGAAAACUACUACCGAUUGGCUGACGAUCUCUCCAAUGCAGCUCGUGAGCUUAGGGUGCUGAUUGAUGAUUCACAAAGUAUUAUUUUCAUUAAUCUGGACAGCCACCGAAACGUGAUGAUGAGGUUGAAUCUACAGCUGACCAUGGGAACCUUCUCUCUUUCGCUCUUUGGACUAAUGGGAGUUGCUUUUGGAAUGAAUUUGGAAUCUUCCCUUGAAGAGGACCAUAGAAUUUUUUGGCUGAUUACAGGAAUUAUGUUCAUGGGAAGUGGCCUCAUCUGGAGGCGCCUGCUUUCAUUCCUUGGACGACAGCUAGAAGCUCCAUUGCCUCCUAUGAUGGCUUCUUUACCUAAAAAGACUCUUCUGGCAGAUAGAAGCAUGGAAUUGAAAAAUAGCCUCAGACUGGAUGGACUUGGAUCAGGAAGGAGCAUCCUAACAAACCGUUAGGAACAGCCCCGUGGAUACUGAAGUUUUUUUUAUGGUAGUUACAGGAAACUUCUGAUACUCUUUUUAUUAUUUUCUUGUAUAGAGUCAGACACUUGAAAAAAACUAAUGUUUGAAGACAAAAAUAUUUUGGCAGUCACAAUACCAGAACUGGAUUGCAUUUCCAGAAUUCUGAGUUAAAGAAACAAAGUAUUUGCUUUGUAAAAGGCCAAAAUUCUAUUUCCUACAAACUUUAAAUGCUGUUUUUAUAGAUGUGAUAUGAGGCAACACAAGCACAGACAGUUGCAUAGAUUUUAAUUUAUACAUAUCAAGAAAAGUGCAAUUUCAUGCUGAAUGAAGCGUAGGAACUUGACAAGCCCAUAGGUAGCUAUAGUUCUUUGUCAGUAUAGGGAAUUAUGUUCAUGUGAAUUUCCUGAUUCUCAGGUGACUAAAAAGCUAGCAUUCUAUGUAUUAACCUUACAACAGACUCUGUAAGUUUGAGCUUUAAAAACCAAACUUUGACAUAACCUUAUUUCUUGUAUUUGCCCCCUUUUUUUUAUAAAAGGUGAAUAAAAAGAAAUAAUUUAAUAUCACCAUUGUAUGGAUUCCUAAUCAAGAUUUCACGUUCUCAGCCCCUGAGACUAGUUUUCUUUGCUCUCUGUAAUUAGAGCCUUUGGAAGCAAAGUUGAAAGGAAGUAUUUCCAUUCUGUUACUGUUUUGUAGCACUUUGUCCAUUUAUUGAUUUUUAAAGUAGAUAUUUAGAUACCACCCCUGCCCUGCCCCAAAAAGAAAAAUGUUUAUUGUCCUGCUAAUCUAUAUGCCUACACCUCAGAAGCUGACAGAUGAGCUUCCUAAAACAUGAGGAUGAAUAAAUGUUAGAACUGUGAUAUCUUCUCAUUUCCACAGAGAUUUGGGUUUAAAACAAAUGGCUAAUAUUUGUAAGCCUGAAAGCUGCCAUCCUCUUUAACAUCCUACCUACCUUUUAAAAUAUUUUCUGGAGGUUAAGUACAGUUAGGCACUAGAACAUUUGUUAAGCCUCCCAAAGUAGUGUGCAUGGAAGAUUCUAGAGUGUCCAGCUCUUGCACUACAAAUGUAAUAAUAACAGAAUAAAUACACUUACCCUGAUGAUAUUGAGGGUACAUGAUUAGCCUAAUGUGAUGUCAUAUGAGGAAGUUUAGGAGUCCAUUUUUCAGGUGGUUUGGUGAUAGGAAUAAAAAUGUUACUCCCGUCGCUGAUUUGGAAGAAAACCGAUGAAGUACAAGUAAGGUUUCCCCACUCCUGUGUGUGGUCAUGGGAAGCCAUUAGAGGGAAGCUGCAGAACAGAAUGGAACAGGACAGGCUGGGCUAGACUCGAGCACGCAGUGGCCCCUGUGCCACCACACUGUGGGUCAGGAACACGCGUCAUGGUGUUCUUGUCGGAAUGUGAACAUACAGCACCCUCUAGCAUUACGAAUCUCUUAGGAUUUUUAAGAUUGUAUUUGAUAAUACUUAUAUUUCACAGGGCACACUUUUGGCACACCUCAGAGCACACUGCUGCUAUUUUGGGUCGUAUCACUGUAAAAUACAUAAUAAGUACUACUUAACUGUGACAUGAAGAAUUGGAAUCCCAGAGGGCAACAUUUGAUUUGACUAAGAUCAGGCAUAAGAUAGAAUUUUUGUCAUUUUUCCUUGCAGUUUUAUUGACUUAGUUUAUGAGCUUGGAUAAAAUAAUUUUUUGAUGAAUCAUGUCAAUAAAAGGAAAAAUAAUGUAACUACCUCAUAAGUCUGAUAAAAGGAAGUUGCUAGUGUUUUAUAGAAUUUCUGAAGGUGGUUAAAUCAAGUAUGAUUUCAAAAUAUCAACUAGUUCCACUUUUGUGAUUGCAGGAUGCUUCUUAUACUAAAGUUCUCAUAAAUAAUAAAUCAGCUUAUGCCAAAAAUAUAUGAAGUUCCUUGGUUUUAAAUUUUGAACUAAAAUGGACUGAGCACAUUAAUUACUGUUUGAAAGUAGGUACCAAACACUGGGUUAUGUGAGUGAGUAAGCAAUCAUAUCGCCUGUCAAACACAUCAAGUGUCGAACACGUCAAGGUGUGAUACUGUCUUUGGAAGGCUCCUAAACAAAUGUGAGCACAAUUAUUAACACCUUAUUCUUCAUGAACACAGACUGUUAAGCAGCACUAACCAAUUUUAUAUUAAAAAGCUAUUUAUUUUGGUGAGUUAUUCCAAGAGUUGUAUACAGCUUUAUUUUUUGGAAUUGCAAUAUUAAAGUUGCACGUUGGAUUUAACUCUCAUGACUUUAGUAAUACCUACAGAGGUGAGCUAAUGGAUGGUACAUGGAGUAGGGACUGCAGAGACCCUAGUUUUGUCCCCACUCCAUCUUCAAAUAAUUUUGGUCUCUUAGGUCUGUGAUACAAAGGCAUAAAACAAUUCCUAUCUUGAAGCCUUGAGAAAAGCUGUUACAUAUACGCAGAUAGUAGCAAGACAGAAAAUGCAAAUAUGUAAAUGUCUUCUGAUAUCUUGAAAUAAAGAUAAAUUUCAGUUAAA